ACAGGCAUGAGCCACUGCGACCGCCAGGAAAUAUUUUUUAAGAGGAUGAUGACUUUUUCCACCAGUGCUUAGAAACUGGACUAUACUGCUCCAAAAGUGAUUCCUAAGAAAAUGUGAGAAAUGUCAGAAUAUGCCACAGCUACGUAUCAUUCCUGACAAAAGUUGACCUGCUCUGAACUCAUGUUUCUCCUUUCCUCCUUCAGUGUUUGAUUUCUUUUUUUUUUUUUGAGAUGGAGUCUCGCUCUGUUGCCCAGGCUGGAGUGCCGUGGCGCCAUCUCAGCUCACUGCAAGCUCCGCCUCCCGGGUUCACGCCUUUCUCCUGCCUCAGCCUUCUGAGUAGCUGGGACUACAGGCGCCUGCCACCACGCCCGGCUAAUUUUUUGUAUUUUUAGUAGAGACGGGGUUUCACCAUGUUAGCCAGGAUGGUCUCGAUCUCCUGACCUCGUGAUCCGCCCACCUUGGCCUCCCAAAGUGCUGGGAUUAUAGUCGUGAGCCACCACGCCUGGCCCAGUGUUUAAUUUCUACAGAAACAUCCUGUCCCUUCUGCAAGGAAAAACAACAGGAAUAUUGGUAGACCAGGCUGGCCUUUCACAAAGGACCACUGGUAUAAUUCUAGGGGUAUCUGCAGAUCCUUCAACCCAAAAAUCCUCCCCAUCAGCCUGCUUCAGAUGCCUCCAGGUCUUUAGCUGUGACAUUAUCCUCUGUUGAAUGCUAACAUCCUUGGGAGGUAAUCUAGGAAGUUUUUUUUGUUUGUUUGUUUGUUUUUUUGAGAUAGAGUUUCACUCUUGUUGCCCAGGCUGGAGUGCGAUCUCAGCUCACUGCAACCUCUGCCUCCGGGUUCAAGUGAUUCUUCUGCCUCAGCCUCUUGAGUAGCUGGGAUUACUGGCACCCACCACCAUGCUUGGCUAAUUUUUGUAUUUUUAGUAGAAAUGGGGUUUCACCAUUUUGGUCAGCCUGAUCCUCCCAAAGUGCUGGGAUUACAGGCGUGAGCCACCAUGCCCAGCCGUCUAGGAAGCUUUUAACAGCUUAGAGUGCAUUUGCAUUAAUUGAUCUGAUCCCCUUUUACCUGAGCACUAACCAUUAGCAGUUUCCGGCAGGGAGGGGCCUCCAGGUCCUUCUUCCCGCCUCCCCAGGCUUUUGAGGUUCUACCACCCUCCAAACUAUACAGUCUUGACUAAGGGUCUUGGGAACCUGGACAGCAUCAGAACAUUACAUUCCUGUCUAAAGAAUGGGGAAGACUAGCUCUACCCAAGGCUCACUUUAUGUGUAACAUUCUGCACUAGGUAAUCUCUAUAAUCUCCAGUACUAGGACUGCCUGCUAGCAGGUUCUCCCAGGACAUCAACAGAGUUUGGGUUAAAUGUUGGGAACCACCAGAACCUCAUACAUGGGAGUGUAAAGUGGUAUAACCAACUUUGGAGAACAAUUUGGCAAUAUCUAAUAAAGUGUGUGCAUCAGACAUUCCUUGCCUAGAAACAUAAAUCCCAAACAUUUGUUCACCAGAAGACAGUCCUCAAUGUUCACAGCAGCAGUAUCCAUAACAGCCCCAAACUGGAAACCACCCAAACGCCGGGUGUUUGUACGUUCACACCACGGAGAGUGAACAACCUACAACUGUACACAACGCGCACGGAGAAUGAACAAUCUACAGCUAUACACAACAUGAACAAAUUUCAGAAUGACACAGGUGAAGCAAAUCAUGGAGGAGGCUGUCACCAGGAAGUUUGUGCAUGAAGACAGCAGCCACAUCAUUGCUUUAUGUGCAGCAGAUCCCCACCAAGGGCUCACCAGGUGCCAGACACCGUUCACCGUGCAAGGAAAUGGCAGUGACAAGAUGGACAGAGUCUCUGCCGCAGGAGCUUACAUUCUGUUGGGGAGACAGACAGGAAACAAAUGCGCAAGUGCAGUGGAGGCUUGCCUCUUGCAUCAGCUGAGACGCCGUGCCGCUGGCUUCCUGCGCAGUGACAAGAUGGCAGCCCUGUUCACCAAGGUGGGGAAGACGUGCCCAGUGGCGGGGGAGAUUUGCCACAAGGUACAGGAGCUGCAGCAACAAGCAGAGGGCAGGAAACCCUCAGGGGUCAGCCAGGAGGCCCUGCGGAGACAGGGCUCAGCCAGCGGGAAGGCCCCGGCCCUCAGCCCUCAGGCCUUGAAACACGUAUGGGUACGCACGGCGCUCAUCGAGAAAGUUCUGGACAAGGUCGUGCAAUACCUGGCGGAAAACUGCAGCAAGUACUACGAGAAGGAGGCACUGCUGGCAGACCCUGUGUUCGGCCCGAUCCUGGCCUCUCUUCUAGUGGGACCCUGUGCCUUGGAAUACACUAAGCUCAAGACAGCCGAUCACUACUGGACUGACCCCUCUGCUGAUGAGCUGGUCCAGCGGCACCGCAUCCGGGGUCCACCUACUCGCCAGGACUCCCCUGCAAAGCGCCCAGCCCUGGGGAUCCGGAAACGGCACUCAAGCGGCAGCGCGUCGGAGGACAGGCUGGCUGCCUGUGCCCGCGAGUGUGUGGAGUCCCUGCACCAGAACUCACGGACGCGGCUGCUCUAUGGCAAGAACCACGUGCUGGUGCAGCCGAAGGAGGAUAUGGAGGCGGUCCCUGGCUACCUCUCCCUGCACCAGUCUGCAGAGAGCCUGACUCUGAAGUGGACCCCCAACCAGCUCAUGAAUGGGACUCUGGGGGACUCCGAGCUGGAAAAGAGCGUUUACUGGGACUAUGCCCUCGUGGUGCCCUUCAGCCAGGUCGUGUGCAUCCACUGCCACCAGCAAAAGAGCGGUGGCACGCUUGUGCUGGUGAGCCAGGAUGGCAUCCAGAGGCCGCCGCUGCAUUUCCCACAGGGAGGACACCUGCUGUCCUUUCUGUCCUGUCUGGAGAAUGGGCUGCUGCCUCGGGGACAGCUAGAGCCCCCGCUGUGGACCCAGCAAGGGAAGGGGAAAGUGUUCCCCAAGCUACGGAAACGAAGCAGCAUUCGCUCCGUGGAUAUGGAGGAGAUGGGCACGGGGCGGGCCACCGACUAUGUGUUCCGGAUCAUCUACCCCGGCCACAGGCACGAGCACAUCACUAUUAACUACCACCACCUAGCGGCCAGCCGCGCGGCCUCGGUGGACGAUGAUGAGGAAGAGGAGGAUAAACUGCACGCGAUGCUCUCAAUGAUCUGCUCGCGGAACCUCACAGCUCCCAAUCCGAUGAAAGACGCUGGUGACAUGAUCGAGAUGCAGGGCUUUGGGCCCAGCCUGCCAGCCUGGCACCUGGAGCCCCUGUGCAGUCAGGGCUCCUCCUGCCUCUCCUGCUCCUCCAGCAGCUCCCCACAUGCAACCCCCAGCCACUGUAGCUGCAUCCCCGACCGGUUGCCGCUCAGGCUACUGUGUGAGAGUAUGAAGAGGCAGAUCGUGUCCCGGGCCUUCUACGGCUGGCUGGCACACUGCCGCCACCUGUCCACGGUGCGGACCCACCUGUCGGCGCUGGUGCACCAUAGCGUUAUCCCACCUGACCGGCCCCCGGGGGCCUCCGCGGGCCUCACCAAGGACGUGUGGAGCAAGUAUCAGAAGGACAAAAAGAACUACAAAGAGCUGGAGCUGCUGCGGCAAGUUUACUACGGAGGCAUAGAGCACGAGAUCCGCAAGGACGUCUGGCCCUUUCUGCUUGGCCACUACAAGUUCGGCAUGAGCAAGAAGGAGAUGGAGCAGGUGGACGCAGUGGUGGCAGCAAGGUACCAGCAGGUGUUGGCAGAGUGGAAGGCCUGCGAGGUGGUGGUGAGGCAGCGGGAGCGGGAGGCCCACCCAGCCACACGCACCAAGUUCUCCUCAGGCAGCAGCAUCGACAGCCACGUGCAGCGCCUCAUCCACCGAGACUCCACCAUCAGCAACGAUGUGUUUAUCUCAGUGGAUGAUCUGGAACCCCCGGAGCCCCAGGACCCUGAAGAUUCCAGACCAAAACCUGAGCAGGAAGCAGGACCCGGGACUCCGGGCACCGCCGUGGUGGAGCAGCAGCAUUCCGUGGAGUUCGACUCUCCAGACUCAGGACUGCCCUCCUCUCGCAAUUACUCCGUGGCCUCGGGCAUCCAGUCAAGCCUAGAUGAGGGGCAGAGCGUGGGCUUCGAAGAGGAGGACGGCGGUGGGGAGGAAGGCUCCAGUGGGCCCGGCCCUGCAGCUCACACUUUGAGGGAGCCCCAGGAUCCCAGCCAGGAGAAGCCUCAGGCCGGAGAACUGGAGGCCGGAGAGGAGCUUGCGGCUGUGUGUGCGGCUGCCUACACUAUAGAAUUACUGGACACUGUGGCCUUAAACCUGCACCGCAUAGACAAGGAUGUGCAGAGGUGUGACCGCAACUACUGGUACUUCACGCCCCCCAACCUCGAGAGGCUCAGAGACGUCAUGUGCAGCUACGUGUGGGAGCACCUGGACGUGGGCUAUGUGCAGGGCAUGUGCGAUCUGCUGGCGCCUCUCCUGGUCACCCUCGACAAUGAUCAGCUGGCCUACAGCUGCUUCAGCCACCUCAUGAAGAGGAUGAGCCAGAACUUCCCCAACGGGGGUGCCAUGGACACCCACUUUGCCAACAUGCGCUCCCUCAUCCAGAUCCUGGACUCAGAGCUGUUUGAGCUGAUGCAUCAGAAUGGAGACUACACCCACUUCUACUUCUGUUAUCGCUGGUUCCUGCUGGAUUUUAAGAGAGAACUGCUGUAUGAGGAUGUGUUUGCUGUGUGGGAGGUGAUCUGGGCAGCCAGGCACAUCUCAUCGGAGCACUUUGUCCUGUUCAUCGCCCUCGCCCUGGUGGAGGCCUACCGAGAGAUCAUCCGUGACAACAACAUGGACUUCACUGACAUCAUCAAGUUUUUCAAUGCUCUUCACGUUUCCCCCCAGAACGUGCUGAGCAUCACGAUGCCCAGGAGAUCCUGCGGAUUGCCCGGGACCUCGUCCACAAGGUACUUCCCUGAAAACCACGUGUAAGAAGUGAUGCUUUUGCCAGUGGAUGAUCUGGAAUGCGACCGGAGCACUUGCUCUGAGGAAUCCCAGGGUGACUCUGUCGGGGAAGAAUCCGGUCACAGCCUCCCCUCAGAGACAGGCCUCAGUUCGAGGGCAGCCCAUUAUCUGUCGCAGACAUCUGCCAUGUCCCUGAGACUGCGGGAGGCAGGGGAUGCAUGGGUGUCCCCAUCUGUCCCUGGUGAGAAGCAAGGCUAGCUCUGCCUUCCACAUGCUUCUCAGGAUGCCAAGAGGCCUAGGAACCCAGAAACCCCCUUGGAGGAGCUGUGUAUGCGGGGGUGCCAGGAAGGGCAUAGCUCCUGCCCCCAGGCCUAGGCAUGCUGCUUGCUCGGCCAUCCCCACUUCCUCCUCUACCCCAACACAUGCAGGCUAGGCCUUGCCCUGGAACAUGGAGGCCCUGCCCGGGGCUGGGGCCUAGUCCAGCAGCCACCAAAGUCUGGCAGACUUUCUGCAUUUGAGAAACAUGACAAAGGGCCCCGCAGCCCUUCUGCACCCAGCACAGCCUGCCCAGCCCAGCCCUGCCCCCGGGCACUGCACAGCCUGUCUGGGGGCCAGACCACCCCAUUGUCCAUCCUUGUUGUCCGUGAGUCCUUGGCCUCCACCAAGCACGUGUGGCCAUUGUGUGCCUGCCUUAGUGACUCCGUGGUUUUGUGAGGAGCAGAGUGUGUAUGAUUUUUGCCUCAGAAACUAUACUCUUCUGUGUAACAGACCAAUAAACAACAUUUGUCAACA